GUCUUUGGUAGUUUUUUUGCACUAACUUCAGGAGCCAGCUCGUGAUCUCAGGAUGUAUGGAAAAAUAAUCUUUGUAUUACUAUUGUCAGGAAUUGUGAGCAUAUCAGCAUCAAGUACCACUGGUGUGGCAAUGCACACUUCAACCUCUUCUUCAGUCACAAAGAGUUACAUCUCAUCACAGACAAAUGGGAUAACACUCAUUAAUUGGUGGGCGAUGGCUCGUGUUAUUUUUGAGGUGAUGCUUGUUGUUGUUGGAAUGAUCAUCUUAAUUUCUUACUGUAUUCGAUGACUGAUAAAGGUUUUCAUGCCUCUGGGAUUGAGAUUAGAGGAAGAAAGCAAAGAAAGGACAUUUUUUUACUUCACUGUUCAUGGUGUAAUUGUGUGCCUGACGGCUGUAGCUACUAACUUGGCUUACGUUGACUGGCUACUAAGGGACUCUAGGAGUCAGAAACUAAAUGCUGAGUCUCUCAAAGGCGUAGAGAGAAUUUCAGAGGGCCUUACCAUGACAUGAGGAUUAAACUCCAGUUCUGCCCGAUUCUCAUCACGAAAUCCUUAUCCCAUGCCUCAUUGUGUUUGGUGUCCCCUUGCCUAGGGGACAGUCCUCCUGGGUAAGAUCAGCAAGAUAACUCUUCAGUCACAUUCCAUUUGAUACUUUGAAUACUCUGAGGUCCUUACCCACCAAAUGGAUGGAAUUCAGCUGCUCAAUCACUGCCUUUCUCAGAACUCGGUUGUCCAACCACAAUUCCCUUUCCCUUAGGAUAGGGCUAUAUUGGCAAAAUGCCGCCCGAACAGACUGCUGACAGUAAACCAAAUAUUAGUUUCUCUCACCUUCUUGAAGGCAUUUACAGUCUUUGUAAGCUUUUCUCCUAGAUUUUCCCUUUCCUGUUCCUGCUUAGAUUCUAAGAAUGAAGUGCAUCCUUCUCCUUUUCUUCAUUAGGUGAAGUGGGAUUUACCCAUUACCAUAUAUUCACCACCAGGUCACUGACGAGAGACUCCAGUGAAUCGCUUUCCCUCUGCAUUCCUCUCCUUGUACAGACUAGAGGGUCACAUUGUGUAAAGCCUAACAUAGCCCUGCAAAGAGAUCUGGCCCCAGCAGUGAACACAAACUCAGUAAUUCUCUUUAGAGUGAGGUGGUAAUCAGUGCCUCUUGGUUUCAGCCGUGGUCCUAGUGGCUACUUAUGGAAGAAUAGGAAUAGUUCCACAACAUCCUGUAACAUUGGCUUACCUGUAUAUUAUAUGCCACCCGUAACCAUAAAAACACCAGGAUUUAGGUUCCUUGAAGGUAAUGACUAUGGGUCCCUCUCUGUGGAAGAAUACUGAAUAGAAGAGAGAAAUCACUCAAUAUGUGGAAUGACUGAUAUGGUUUGGCUGUGUUCCCACUCAAAUCUCAUCUUGAAUUGUAGUUCCAAUAAUCCCCACAUGUCAUGGGAGGAACCCAGUGGGAGGUACUUGAAUCAUUGCGGUGGUUUCCCCUGUGCUAUUCUCAUGAUAGUGAGUAAAUUCUCACAUAAUCUGAUAGUUUUAUAAAGGAGCUUCCCCCUUCACUCAGCUCUCAUUCUUCUCCUUCCUGCCACUAUGUAAGAAAGAUGUGUUUGUUUCCCCUUUGGUCAUGAUUGUAAGUAUCCUGAGACCUUCCCAGCCAUGCAAAACUGUAGAUCAAUAAAACCUCUUUCCUUUAUAAAUUACA